GCCCCCGCCUGCUGCCGCCGCGCGGCCCUGCCGGCGCACCCGAGCCCCACUCCCUGCGAGGGCCGCGCGGAGGGGCGCGCAGGAGGAGGAGGAGCCGAGGACCGCGGAGGGGAGGAGGGGAGUCGCCUGGGGAGCCGAGGGCUCCUCGCGCAAGUGCCCGCAGCGCCCGGAAGCGUCCAAAGGCCCCGAUGCUGGGAGAAGACGUGGAGGCCUCUCGGGGAACCACGACGACCUCCACGAUGACGCAAUAGUCAUGCCAAAUUAUACAUGCAUAUUUCACCUCCACCCGGAAGGCCAGAGCCAUCCUCUCGGCCUCUAAGUGCACAACGGAACUAGAAAUCAAGGAGGAGAGACCAAAAGGGUAAAAAAAAAAAAAAAAAAAUUUAAGGCGCGUGGGGUGGUGGCGGUCCUUGAGCUGGAAAGCAGGAACCCUGGCUUAUUGCGUGGUCCCCCCCACCACCACCACCCCACGCCUUCCGUAGCACGAGCUUUAAUCAUUUACUAUGAAACCGGUAACUAAGGGAGAUACAGCGUGUUGAACCACUGAAGCACGCCCCUCCACACACACACCAGCCAGAAAAAGGAUACCCCGUCGGCUCCGGACCCGGCAAAUGUACCUGGGCUCCCCCUGGAGGCCACAUUCUCCGAGGUCGCCUUUCGGUCCCCAAUGUUCCUCAAAGGUAUUCCGUUGUAAUCCCGGAGAACUGAUACACACUAGUGCUCUGAAACUUGGCCUGUGCUCGAGGCGGCAACCCCUGCCCCUCUGCCUGGCGAUGCCGGAACACACCCAUCUGGCCAGGUCCUGUUCACUGGCCAAGAAUGCAGCAUUGAACACUGGGCAUUGGGGCGGGGGUGCACUCUGCGCUGACACCGCACCCCUCCCCUCAACUUGCUGACUAGAGGUAAUCGCUUCCUUUCAUCGAUUCACAGCGUUAGAAAAAUGCAGCAUUGAGAGGCAGCGCGGAGGUCAACUGGACCAUCACCCUUAGGUUGUAGGGAAGAAAACUGAGACCUAGAAAGGUGAAGCGGUUGUCCCAAAGGCUUCCAGCUGCUCCCAGUACUCAAGGACUUGGAGCACACUUGGGGAAAUGCUCACUGUUGUAUUCCCGUUCCUCACUAUCCAGGAGGCCUGAACUCUCAAACUCCGAAUCUGAUUUCCACUCUCCCAGGAAGUCUUCGGAAAUCACUGUAAGUUCCUUGCAGAUUCUCAUUGAGCCUCUCCCCAGGACCCACCCUUUGGCCCUGCGUGUCUGCGACUAGGUGGAUUGUCAAUACAGGAGUCCAUACUGACUGAAUCCCUAAUUUUGGCCUGUAUUCUUCUCCCUCUGUGAACCAUCUUCUUAGAAGUCACUGAACCAAGAGUGCCAGAAAACCAUCCCAAGACUCACACAGAGUUGUUCUUCCAUAGUGGAUGUUUUGGCCACUGGACAUCAGAACCACAUUUUGGGUUUGAAGAAUCUUCUACAUGUGAUGAUCCAGUAAAUGAUUUCAUAGUCCACCAAACGGUCACGGUUCACACUUGGAGACACCCAAUGCAGGUCUCUGCUGGCUGAGUGCACUGGCUUGUGGCUGGAGAUGAAGAAACUGAGGGCUUGAGGGGUAUACUGCUUUGCCAAAGUCGUACAAAUGGUAAGUGCAGAACCAGGAUCUGAAUUCCGUCAGUCUGACUGCAGAGUCCACGCCGACACCGUGGAAGCUGGUGAUGCCCAUUAGGCCCUGUCUGGGCAUGAAGAGGAUGCCCUCCCUCAUGAGCUGGAACACAGCAUCCCCUGUUGUGGGUGUGGCUCUCUUAAAGACCAUCUGGUGAAUUUUGCUUGUGCUGGUUUCUUAUUAAACAACCUUCAGAUUUGGCUUCACGUGCAACUCACAUAGAGGGAAAGGAGACCAUGAUCCGCCAACAUGACAGCUGUAUUUUUCAUUAGUAAAUUAGCAAACUGGCUGCCUGGGUCACCAUGCAUACCUGUUAAGGUGAGCCCGCCCCAGAGCUAAAGGCUACCAUGUGCCAACUUAACUGAGAUUCUGAGUGUGCAAGGAUAACCCCCGUCAUGGCCCCGGGUGCCAAGGAAAUCCCUUUUAGCCUCCUCUUGGCAGACUUGGCCAGCCUUCCCCAGUGACAGCCUGGCUCUUUGGAUUCAAGCUGCCUGGUCAGACUGCAAGGGUCAUCUGUACAAAGAAGGAAGCAACAGUGCCAGGUUCCAGCGUGCGUUCCAAGUUCCACAUUCUGUGUGCAGACUCCCAACGCCAGAGCAAAGGCAGGCCCCUGGCAGGGGACUGCUGAGAAAGUGGAACUCCAGAGACACUCCUGAAAUUGUCCUAAGUCAAAGGAGCCAAACGGUGUACGAGCUCCCUCUCUGCCGUCCCCUCUGAGAGCAGCCAUGGCCCUGAGUGAUGUCGAUGUGAAAAAGCAGAUUAAGCACAUGAUGGCUUUCAUUGAGCAGGAAGCCAAUGAGAAAGCAGAGGAAAUCGAUGCCAAGGCUGAGGAAGAGUUUAACAUUGAGAAAGGACGCCUCGUGCAAACCCAACGACUGAAGAUUAUGGAGUAUUAUGAGAAAAAGGAGAAGCAGAUAGAGCAGCAGAAGAAAAUCCUGAUGUCCACCAUGAGGAAUCAGGCGAGGCUGAAAGUCCUGAGAGCCCGAAAUGACCUCAUCUCAGAUUUGCUCAGUGAGGCGAAGCUGAGACUCAGCAGGAUUGUGGAGGACCCAGAGGUCUACCAGGGGCUGCUGGAUAAACUGGUGCUCCAGGGUCUGCUCCGACUGCUGGAACCUGUGAUGAUUGUACGCUGCCGGCCACAAGACCUCCUCCUGGUGGAGGCUGCUGUACAAAAAGCCAUCCCCGAGUACAUGACAAUUUCCCAGAAACAUGUGGAGGUCCAGAUUGAUAAAGAGGCAUACCUGGCUGUGAAUGCAGCUGGAGGUGUGGAGGUCUACAGUGGCAAUCAGAGAAUAAAGGUUUCAAAUACCUUGGAAAGCCGACUGGAUCUCUCAGCCAAGCAAAAGAUGCCAGAAAUACGAAUGGCCUUGUUUGGUGCUAACACCAACAGAAAGUUCUUUAUAUAAGCCUCUGGGAAGUGAAGCUAGUGUUGAACCACUAAACCAUAAAAGUUUAAGUUUUUUGGGGAAAGGAAACUAGUAGUGUUUCCUCCUCUUUGAUGCUCUGAUACUGUUCUGUUUUUCUUCACGAAAUACCCUUUGGAUAGCUAAAGUGUUAACUUUGAAAUAAAGCCCAAAUUAAUGCUCAGAA